ACAUCUAGGAUGAUAACCAUUUCUCACCACUUCUGCUGCUUCCACCAAGUUCUAUCAUCUCUGUCACCUGGAUUACUGCAAAAGCCUUCUGAAGGGCUUCCCUGCUUCCACCCUUACUGCUCCACACUCUAUUCUUAACACAGCAGCCAGAGUCUAUUAUGUCACUCUGCUUGAAACUCUCCAGUGGCUUUUUAUCUCAGAAGUGACAGAGUCCUCACCAUGGUCUAUACAACCCUUGCAUGGAGUGCGGCUUCAUCUGCUAUCACUCUUGCCUUUGCUGACUCUGCUCCAGCCAUACCUCAGGACCUUUGCACUUGUUUCCUCUGCCUGGAAUGCUCUUCCCCUCAGAUGUCUGCAUGGCUUUCUUAUUUAUUUCAUUCAGGUGAAAAGUCAUUUUUCUGGAGAGGCCUUCUUAGACCACUCCAUCUAGAAUAGUAUCCCUCACCUAUCCCAUCAUUUUCUGCCCCCUUACCUUGCCUUGUUUUCUUUCGAGUAUUUAUAGAACUGUCAUACACAGACCAGCACACACACACAACAUUUGUCUUUCACUGGUAGAAGACAAGCUCCAGGAUGGCCAGUAAUCUGCCUUGUUCACUGUGAUGUCCAUAGCACAUAGAAUGGUUUCUGACAUAUAUUAAGCACUCAAAGAGAUAUGUGUUGAACUAAUGAAAAAGGGAACAGAAGACAGAGCAAUAGGGAUCAUUCUGCCAUUUCUCCCAUCCAAGUACUAACCAGGCCCAACCCUGCUUGGCUUCCAAGAUCAGAGGAGAUCGGGCACAUCCAGGAUGGUAUGUCUGUAGAGUGUUCUGCUAUUUCUUUCCCACUAUUCCAUCCAUUUUUUUCUAAGAGAAGCAAUGUCUAUAGAUACACCAACAUCUCCUAAGUCUCUCGUCUUCUGUCCUACUUUCCCAAAAAUAAUAGUCUUAUCUUCCUUAAAAAGGGAAAGGUCAAAUAAGUAGAAAGGUGAGGAUUUUGGUCCCUCCCACAGUGGCAGACCGGAGCCCUCUGUCUAUAUCCUGGGCAAACUGGGCAGGGCCAUUCAGUGCCUAUCUCCAGGGUGUUGGCCUCUUGUGCUAAUUUAAGAAGAGUGAAGUUUUUUGGAAAUUUGAGAAAAUGGAAAUUCAUUUCUUAUUUAUUUAUUCAAUAGAAACGGGGUUUCACCAUGUUGGCCAGGCCCCUGAGAAGGGAAAUUGUCUUGCCAUCGCUAAAACAAGAUUGGUUCUUGAAGAGAGUAAUUUUUCCCUUCUAUAGCCUUCACUUUUUAUGCCACUUGCAGAUUUUCUUGGACUGUAUUUGUUCUUCUGCCUCUUGGUCAGGAAGUUUGAGUUUAUGAUUUGGUUUCCCUUAAGCUAGGUGCAGACAUGAGCCCUGAACUGGAGGCAGAGAUAAAGGGUUUGUAAUUUACUUAUGUUCGUAGGGUAAGGUGUGUGGAGUAGAGAGCAUUCAGCUCUGUUUGGACUCUCUGGUUUUGCAGGUACUUGUAUGAUUGAGGUCUAGUAAUACUCAUAUUUUAUUUAUUGUCAAGUAAAAUUAGAUGCCUCUCUUACGAGGAAUGCUGAAAGUUUUGUUCCUCCUUUCCUGUUUUUUUUUUUUUUUUGGUUGUUUGUUUUUCGUCUGUAUAUGUUGCCCUUAAACAGAAGUUUACCAUGUAGUGCUUUAGUCAGCCAACCUCCCGUGUGUGGAGUGAGAGUUUUGAUUCUAAUGUGGGGAUGGAGGUGGGGUGCCAGAUUUAGCAAACUAAAAAAAAGUUAAAUUUGCAUUGCAGAAAAACACUAAAUAAUUGUUUCCUAUAUCUUAUACAUUAUUUGGGACAUACUUUUACUAAAAAAUUGUUCUUUAUCCAAAAUGCACAUUUAACUGGAUGUCUUGUUUUGUGUCUGGCAGCCCUAGCUGGAGUUUAUGUUUAUGCAUAGGAAAUGCAUCGAUGGUGAAAAUGUCCAAAGAAUGAUUGAGCCAUGGCUGAUUUUUGGUGAUUGUGCAUGUAUCCAAAAGAGAAGAUUUGUAAACCCAAGGAGUAUUAGAAUUAGAAGGAAGUUAGAGAACAUUUCAUUUUACUCUAGUCUUUUAUAGUUAAUGGAAUUUACUCCAGAGAGGUUAAGUCACUUUGUCAAAGUCACAUAGAGUUAGUGGCAGAGCUGGAAGUGGGACUCUGGAACCAGCAGUUGUUCUGCUGCAUAAUCCCUUCCCUUAAGAGGUCAUGAAGAAGUUGCUUAUGUUUUCAUGUUGACCUUUAAUCACAUCUCUAGCCAUCCACUCAAGAUCACCUCAUUAUCAUACUGUCCUUCAGUCCCCAGAUCCAACAUGUGGCAGCCAAAGCCAUUCUCAUGAGACACUUUGACUUUUCUCUGAGAGCCGCAUAACUGUUGAAAGCCCCAUGUGGUUCUUGUCCCUGCUGUUAUGCCAGAAAGCCUGUAAUUCAAUGUGGUUUUAUUUUUUUUUAUGGUUUUGUUAACACUUUUGACCCUCUGGAGUAUUUAUUAUAAGGUGCUUUGAUUAAGGUGGUCUUACUGAGUAUAAUUCCACAACAACUAAGUGUUGUCUUAUGGAAAGCCUGCUUGCUUUGAGUGGCCUAUUCCCACAAAAUUCCUCACCCCUUUUUAUUUUGGUACAAUAAAUAUGGAAGAUAUACAUAUGACAAGGACCAAGGUAGAUAGACAGGUGUAUGUGACUUGCUCACUAGAGAUCUGUUCUUUUUAAACAAGAUUUUAUUAUUUUUUAUUGUAAUUAUUUGUACCUAUUUAAAAGAAAGCAGCCUUGAAAAUGAACUGCUUUCUCUAACUGCUAUUUGAAUACCAUAUUUCAGAACCACUAAUCUUGUUUUUUCAUAGUUUCAUUGGUUAAUUCAUAUAAAGUCUUACCAGCUGCCAGGUCAAAGCAUAAUAAUAAAAUUGGUUGCCACGAGACUGAAAAGUCUGUUCAUUCUUAUUUGCUAUAGUUUAUCUACCUUGGCCUGAUCCCACCACCUGGGAGGCUGGUCAAGUCCUAUCAGGGUAUGGCUAAAUACUAAUCUGCUGUGUAUUUGUAUCGUUAAAAGCAAAGUCAAGGUCUAAAUCAGCUAGUUAAACACAAUAAUAUGAUACUUUUGUUCUUGCUGUACUAGCCCUAAUAAGGGGAGAAAUGAAACAUACAGAAAUAGGUCAUGACUUAAAUGUUCAUUUACAAAACUAAAGAAUUUUAAAAUAUAACCUAUGAUUGUGGUCAGGAUUUCUUUGUUUCUUGCUAAGAAAUCAUUAUGAAAAUAGUGAUUUUCAUAAUAAAUCGCAUCAUUUCAAGGAAACAACUCCAAGAAUGAGUGAAGAGGUGUAACAGUCCUUGAAAAGAUAAGUCAUUGUCCUCACAGUCAAAUACUGGAGACCUAAUGUGGCUUUUCUCAUUAGGGACAAGGUCAGCUGUCCCAGGUCCCACGUCUGCCCUAGGCUGUGUAUUGAAGUGGGUUGUGUAGUGAAGUGGGUUGUGGUAUUUCCUCAGGUGGCGGCUCAUUCCUGUGUUCCGGACUUCCUGCUUGAAUGUGGAAGAAUCAACACAGUCAGGAAUCAGUCGACAAAAAGUAACCUUCCUGAAGAGGACAUGUGAUUGGAAGUUGUCAAUUGUUGAAGCAUUGGUAACUCCAGUCUCUAACGUUUUAGAAAAUCAUAACAAGCGGUUCUCUACCCUGUAAAGGUGAACUACUGAGUUCUUCAUUAUGUCUGAUGGAGAUUAUGAUUACCUCAUCAAGUUUUUAGCUUUGGGAGACUCUGGUGUAGGGAAGACCAGUGUACUUUACCAAUAUACAGAUGGUAAAUUUAACUCCAAAUUUAUCACAACAGUGGGCAUUGAUUUCAGGGAAAAAAGAGUGGUGUACAGAGCCAGUGGGCCGGAUGGAGCCACUGGCAGAGGCCAGAGAAUCCACCUGCAGUUAUGGGACACAGCAGGGCAGGAGAGGUUUCGUAGCUUAACGACAGCGUUCUUCAGAGAUGCUAUGGGUUUUCUUCUACUUUUUGAUCUGACAAAUGAGCAAAGUUUCCUCAAUGUCAGAAACUGGAUAAGCCAGCUACAGAUGCAUGCAUAUUGUGAAAACCCAGAUAUAGUGCUGUGUGGAAACAAGAGUGAUCUGGAGGACCAGAGAGUAGUGAAAGAGGAGGAAGCCAUAGCACUCGCAGAGAAAUAUGGAAUCCCCUACUUUGAAACUAGUGCUGCCAAUGGGACAAACAUAAGCCAAGCAAUUGAGAUGCUUCUGGACCUGAUAAUGAAGCGAAUGGAACGGUGUGUGGACAAGUCCUGGAUUCCUGAAGGAGUGGUGCGAUCAAAUGGUCAUGCCUCUACGGAUCAGUUAAGUGAAGAAAAGGAGAAAGGGGCAUGUGGCUGUUGAGAAGUCAAGUAAGCGACAUAGUAGUUCAGGUGGCCCAUGCCUGGGAUCUUCUCUAUGAUUGAUACAUGGCACAGUGAGAGAUUAAUGGGCAUUGUGUACAAAUUGCUUCUCACCAUCCCCAUUAGACCUACGAAUAAAGCAUCCGGUUCUAAAAUUAAUUUGUUGCAGCUUUGUAAAUAUUUCUUUAAGAUUCAGCCUGAGAGUUAGGAGAAAUAUUUCAGAGCCAAAAGUGCCUUAUACAACCUUAGCCUAUUAUAGUAAAUCAUUCAAGGAUUCAGAAUUUUGCAGUCACAGAAGAGUGUAUUUAUUAUGUAGAAUGAAUGAGGGUACUGUCACCUGCCUUAAUGUAGGUAGGCCCAGAGUCUUACAUUUAAGAUCUUACAUGCAGUUAUAAAACCGCCACAGUCUUCAAUCCAGAUUUGAAGACUCAUGCCAUAGGUGACAUUCUAAAAUACCAUUAAAGCCACUUAAAUGUUAAAUAAGAAUAUACAUGCACAUCAGCUCAAUGUCUUUGAGUAUUAAUUUUAUGUAAGCAUUCUAUUUAACAUGAAUAUAGGACAAAUCAUGGCUAUAUCUAUAGACCUUGGAUAAACUGGAUUGACCAAUUAUACACUCACGGUGACUUUUUUAUUGGUGGGAAGGGGAUUGGGGUGGGGCAGGCUGGCUUAAUGUAAUAUGAGCAACCAAAGUGGGACUUCUGUCUCCCCGCUAUAUUCCCAUUGCUCUGAAUGGUUGAUUGAAGGGUCAGGGAACUAGAUUUUAUGGCUUUAGUUCACUGUGAUUGUACAUUUAUACUUGGCCUAUGUGCUGGCCGCACCUGAACAUAGCUGGUGCUUAUGCCGAGUUAUUUGCGAUGAGUAAAUAUUUAGUUUCUUUUUCUUCAUAUUUAUAAUGUUGAUCUGGCAUCCUCAGGCUGCAGCUUUAUUAGCUUAUAACUUACUCAUCUCUAUCUUUACCAGCAGGCUCUGUAUUGUUGAUAUUUGCAACUUGUUUUGCUUUUCCAUUGGUGGAAUUGAAAUAAUUAGUUUUUAAUUACAUAAGAUGCCUGUUUGCUAUUUGGUGGAAGAUAGAUGUUCAUAUUGAAGCAGUCACAUUUGUACUGUAGUUCAAUAAAAGAAAAAUGAAGUAUUCUGUAGCCUAUAUUUUUCAUAGAGCUCAUGAGCAUUUACUGUACUUGCUGGGUCUUGCCAAGAUCAUUUAUUCCGCUGCAUUGCCAAAGUGUCUUCAUACCAAAUUAAAGGUGGUUUUAAUAUAUGUUUCAUGGAAGUUGUUUAUAAAAUUCAAAGGUAUUUCAUUUAGGUGAAAAGUCUUAUUUAUUAAAGUGGUUUGAAUAAAGUAGAUCAAAACUUCCAGAGAUCUUAAUGGCUAUAUAGGAAGAAAUAUCACUCACCAUAAUUUAAAUAAAGAAUAAAAAUACUUGUAUUUUGUGGUGGCAAAUGUUUGGUAGAACUGUAAUUAGAAAAAUACAAGUAUAUUUGCGUGAUGGUUACACUAGAAGCCCAGACUUUACGACUACACAAUAUAUUCAUGUAUCUAAACUGUACUUGUACCCCCUAAAUUUAUUUUUAAAAAAGGAAAAAUAAAAGUAUCAUGAAAAAACCUAUUUUUUUUUCCACUGUCCUUCCACUACUCCCAUAACAAACUUAUCCAUGGUUGGUAAAAUUUUACAUAUUUCUAUCCUUGAAAUGAAGGCUUCUUUUAAAUUCCAAAGAAGUCAUGGAGGCCUGUGCAUUUGAAUUGUAUAUGCUAGUGAGGAAAAGAUUUAGACAUUUCAAGAGCAGGGUUGGCCAGGCGCGGUGGCUCACACCUGUAAUCCCAGCACUUUGGGAGGCCGAGGAGGGCGGAUCACGAGGUCAGGAGAUCGAGACCAUCCUGGCUAACACAGUGAAACCCCAUCUCUACUAAAAAAAAAAAAAAAAAAAAAAUGGGCUGGGCGUGGUGGUGGGCACCUGUAGUCCCAGCUACUCAGGAGGCUGAGGCAGGAGAAUGGCGUGAACCUGGGAGGCGGAGCUUGCAGUGAGCCGAGAUUGCGCCACUGCACUCCAGCCUGGGCGACAGAGGAGACUCUGUCUCAAAAAAAAAAAAAAAAAAAAAGAGCAGGGUCAUAAUCACACAGCAGUGCCUUAUAUAGUUGCCAUAAGACUUCAGUGCAGUACAACAUAAUUUUACAGCUACAUAUCAGGGCAUAUUCUAUAUGGUGUAUUUGUGUUAGAAUAACACAUUAAAUGUCUUUAAACAUAAAAAUAAGAAUGUUUGCAUGUUUCAGUUUUCAAGAACCAAAUGAGUAAUUAGCUAUAGAUUCCACUGGCCUUAAACAUACAAUUAAGUGUAUACAUGAUAUAGUGCACACACAAAAGCCACCUUUAAUUAUUGAAAUAACCUGUAUUCUUUUUGGAAAUCAUUUAAGUUUGGUAUUGAAGUACUAUAUUUUUUGUGCAUCAAUGUAUUUUUCUAUUUACAAGCCUAUGUAAAAGUGAAGUGUAUCUUCAGUGAACCAUGUGCCAAUUAAGCUGUAAUAAAAAAGUGGUCUAGUCUGUCAAA